AGUGAUGCGCAUCCUUACACAACCUUAUGGGACCUGUCUGCCCUUGUGGAGAUGGGAGCAGGGGAAGACCAAAACCGUGGAUUGUGCUAAAUGCUCCAGAUGUUGUUCUCAGUGUACACUGCCAGGGAGGAGCCACUGUUAUUCCGACUUUACACAUGAGCAAACUGAGUUCAGAGAGGGGAGACCCUUUACCUAAGGUUGCAAGCUUAGUAACAAAUGAACCAGCCUCCAACCUAGGUCCACCCACUGGCCAGCAUGGGUGCUGUUGGUGUAUCUGCCCACUUGUGAAGCUAUCAGAGCCCUCAUGGCAUUGGGAUUCAGUUGUCCAUCACCCUCUAUAAGACACACACAACAAUAGCAUUGUGUGCUAGCAGGUCAUGCAGUGGAGGCUGCUGUGUUUGCUGGGAGGAGAGAUGACUGGGCUGUGGGUAGGAGUCUGCAGGGGUAGAGGGGUGGCCAAAUAGAGAUGCACAGGCUUCCUUUGUCUGUCUUGGCUGCCACAUGGGGCCUUGCUGAGCCUGGAGUGGCCAUUCUGGAUGUAUGGGGGAGGUGUGCUUCCCCUUGAAGGUCCCUGGGCACCUGGACUAGUGGAGGCAGGCUCCUGGCUGGCUCCCUCACCAGACUCCGUGGCGCCAAUGAUGCCCAGCCAGAGGAGCAGGGGGCCAUUGGCCCCCAACCACGUGCAUGAGGUAUGCCUGCACCAGGUGGAGUCCAUCAGCGACCUACAUAGUGGAGCAGGCACACUGCGCCCCUAUCUAACUGAAGAGGCACGACCGUGGGAUGAGCUGCUGGGCGUUUUGCCGCCGUCACUGUGUGCCCAGGCUGGCUGCAGCCCUGUGUACAGACGAGGAGGGUUCCUGCUGCUGCUCGCGCUGCUGGUGCUCACUUGCCUAGUGCUCGCACUCCUGGCUGUCUACCUGAGCGUGCUGCAGAGUGAAUCCCUGCGCAUCCUGGCACACACGCUCCGCACGCAGGAGGAGACACUACUCAAACUCCGCUUGGCCAGCCUCAGCCAGCUUCGGAGGCUCAACUCCAGUGAGGCCCAAGCACCCAGCUGAGAUGCCAUUUGGAUCUGGGGCCUGGGGGUGUGUGUUGGUGGGGGAAUAAAGUGGCUAUGGGCAGGUCUCUCCUUCCCUACUGCUGGCUGCCACAUCUACACUAUUUCCUUGGUGAGAUUUUUGUACAAGAACCUGUUGUUAACUUAAUGGCUGCCUCCCUCUCCUGAUCUCUUCAAGCCAGGCCUAGCCAAGCCUCUGGUGCCAAAGCCUCGCUUUGGGUGGCCCAAGGUCAGGGGAAGGGGCACCAGCCUCCUGGCUCCUCCUGUGGCCUGUCAACACUCUCUGGCCACCCCAGAUGGCAGGUUCUGAAGUCUAGAAAUAGCUGCCCCCAUAGCAAUCACCCAAACUCUGCCAGGGCUCCCAGUGAGGGUCCAGCCUCAGCUCUUAAAGACAGGCUGGGCUCUGAGUAGGGGGAGAGGCACCACCUGGGGAAGACUGCCUUGGAGGGCAAAGGUGACAUCGUGGAAGACCAGUUGGGCCCAAGCCUGGGAUAGUAGAUGGGGAGGGAGAACAGAAAAAUACCCAGGGGUUAAGACCACAGAAGGCUGACCGUUCUGUUUAAUUAUCUGUAAUAAUCCUUAAAAAUCAGCACACAAAUCCAUUCCAGGUAGCUUUGCCACCCCACCUGCUGUGGUGGCAUUUGUCCAGAUGCCACCACCCCCCUAAGAGUGGGUCAUCCUGGGGGAGCAAGGCCUGAGAAAGGAAAGGAAGGGAAAGGCCCCCUAGUGCCUGCCCCACAGCCCUGAGGAAGGCACAUAUUUAGCCUGGCCUGAGACAGGACAGGAAGGGGCCACAGGGCUGAGUGCAGGGACAAAGGGGUCAGGGUCCCAAGUGUCCGGGCCCCCAGCUACCCACCCCAUGUCUGUUUUUGGUUUUGUCAUUAAAAAAAAUAAAGUGACAAAUACUGGUGGA